AGAGUCCAGGGAGAGUGCGCGGGCGGCCGCCGGCUGAAUGAAGCCUGGGACGCGGGAGCCGCGCCGCGCGCAGUGUCUGCAGUGCCGGAGGUCUGGGAGGCUCCGGGCGAAGCCUCCCUGCUGCAGGUUAUGAUGAUGUCAGACAAUGCUAAAGGCAGAGCAGCUCAUUCAUGGAAGAAAAGAGGGAGUAUUUCUUCUCUAAGUAAUCAUGAAUUUUGGCGAAAGGAAAUUCAUGGGCGCAUCAAAGAUUCUAUGAGUACUGUGUCUUAUAUGGAAGAACCCAGUCAGCGUGAUGAUAUCUCUCGCCUUACAGUUCAGAUGGAAAACACCUAUCAGUUGGGAAAAAAAAAAUCUCGAGAAAGAAGAAAAGCUUUGCCAUUCACAUCAGUUUACUCUGAAACUAGUUUUAGGAGCUUAUUUCAGAAGUCAGAAACUGAACAUUGAUGGAUGAUUCUGGAUGUUUAGGGGAAAGGUAACAAAGAAGUAAGAAAAGAAUACUUCAUUACCAUAUUUCAAAGUAUUUUCAAAACAGGAUCUGGUUAAUGACUUUUUUUUUAAUCUAAGCGAAGUAUGGAAAGGACAUUGGUAGCACUGUACAACGGGAACUACUGGAAACAGACUCAAGUGCCACCAGGACCCUCUUUCCAGCACUAACCUAUGUGCACUUUCUUCUCUUUUGGUGGCCUGGCCUCCUUACCACCAUGAAAAACAUGUCCUCCAGCAGGUCCUCAGAGUCACAUGGUAACUUUUGCCACCAGAAAGAGGCUGACUCUUUUUUCCUACUUGCAGUUUAAAAUAAAAAUUCCAAAAAAAGACUCUCAUUGUCCUGGCCUAGAGCAUUGUCACCCUGGGUUAAUCAACCAUGCCCUAGGCUUGGGUUCGCAGGAGAUGAUGGGGAGAUCUUUAAGAACCACUUUCUAGAUUCAAUCUCCACCCCCACCCUUCCACGAUUUAAGUGGAAUUCAACAAUUUCUAUAUUAUCAUCAAAAUAAAAAUAACGAUUUAUAGAACCUCAAGAGGCUCACCUAACUGAACUGCAGUCAGAGGCUGUAACCUUCUGGUUAAGUUCAGCCAGUGGGAAACCUCAGCUGAGAGGCAGAGGGAGUGAGAAGUGUGAGGUGGAGCUGUUUAUUUCCCUGGCUCCUGCCUGUGAGUUCAUCACAGCCUGGUUACAUUCUUCAACCAAAGGACAGAAACUGCUCCCAAGGGAGCCCUCUCCACAUGACCCUUCUGGGAUCUAUUAAAAGCUCUUCCUCUAUUCCCCAAUCUUGGGGUGGGAGGGGUGGGCUGACAACCUUACUUUCACUGGCUGAGGGGUGCUGCACUAUCCCUUGUGAUUUUCUACAGCCCACUCAGAACUUCCUCCUGGAAUUAUUUUAACUAUAGGGUGCCAUAUGUUUCAUUUGACCCUGACAGAUACAGUCAUCACAAACAAACACUUAUUACUAGAUAUUGACAUAUAUUAAAAGAGAAUUGAAUAGAAUUCUUGAUCUCAUUCCUUCAUCUUUAUCAAUUCAACAAAUAAUGACUGGGCUUCUGUAUGCCAGGCCCUGGGCACAUGUUCAUGUCAUGCAAUGACAUUAGUAUAUGACCAAAGUGAUGAUAUGGCUAAUAUUCCUGGGAUGCAGGAGGAAGAAGAUUCAUUUGAAGCUUCUCCUCUGAACGUGGAUGAAAUGUGGUCGAGAAUAUAAGCUCUAGCAUCAGAUAAACCUGGGUGUGCACCCCAGCUCUGCCUCUCUGUGUGAUUCUGGGCAGGUUACUCAAUGUAUAUAAAUCUCUGUUUCCCCACCUGCCAAAUGGAGAUAACAGUGAGAUUCACCUCAGAGAUCUAUUGGAAGACUAUAUAAGGUAAUAUGAAGUGCUUAUCGCACUGCCUGACAUGUAGCAACGGCUUAAUAAAAAGUAUUCAUUAUUAUAUAUGUAUACAAUAUACAGUCAUAUAUCAUAUAUAAUGAUUAUCUAUAAAAUUUAAUUCUAUUUAAAUUCAGAAAUCAUACAUUAAAAAUUUCUUAUGCCUUUAGCAUUGUAUUAGACUCUGAGGAGGAUAAAAUCCGAGCUUGCUUACCAUUUCACUGGAAACGCAGGUAUGCUUUAGCCAAUAUCAAGUGGAUUAGGAGCCAGGAUGGCAGUGGGGACCCAGUGCAUGGAAAGGAGGGACAUUUUUACCUGAGAGGAGGUAGAGUGCUACCUGGAGAAGAAGACAUUUGAGAUGGUCUUGAAACAUGAGUGGCUGUUUCUCAGAUGAACAAGAUGGGGAAAGAUAUUCCAUUUGAAAACUAAAGAGCAAGAGUAAGGACACAGGAGCACCUUUAUAGACAGAUGGAGCCUGUGAGGCUGGAGCAGUCCACAAGAGGGGCACUGUGGUAGCGGGAGAAGGGGCAGUAGGGAAUCACACUUUAGACCUCGCUAAGGGGAAUGUCAUUUAAGAUCUGGUAGAUAGAUUGGAGCGGGAGAUAUAAGAGGUAGAGAGCCAGUUAUAAAGUUGUUGAGACUUUGAAGUAUGUCCACAACAAUGGGGCCUGGGAAGGAAGAGACUUUCAAGGUCAAACCCCAGCAGUAUUGAACACACUUUUGAGAUAGUCACGUAAAUGUACGAAAAUAUUGUCUUCUUGUUCUCUCUCAGAGCACUUGACAGGAAACCUAAUUAGAGCCACUUGUUUCUUUCAAUAGAGUCCACCCAGAAGAUUAAAUCCCUCCAUGUUUCCAUACUCUUUUGAUUAGCCUAUGGGGUGGGUGGGUGUGAUUUGAAAUUACUUUUUAGAAAUAAAUUUUAUGUGUAUUUUCAGGUCCUCCCAAACAUUUUCCUGUGGUCACCGUCAAUCAUAUUUUGAAAGAUGUAGUAACCAGCUAUCUACAAGUAGAAGAAUAUGAACCAGAGCU